AAAUGAAUCCAUUUUAUUGUUUCAUUAUUAGAAAAUAUUUUUACCAGCAAUAUGGAGAGCUCUUAUUGAUAGAAAGCCUUCUGAGAUCUUGGCACCACACUACCUUACCAGUCUAGAAAGCAUUAUUUGCCUACUACAUUAUUGAAUUCUCCUUAUAUACCAUCAAAUGCAGCUGUCUUAUUCGCCAAAUAUAUUUUCACGUGUACAUGACUUUAUUCAGGCCAUUCCUUCAUCCUUGAUACACAAGUGAAAUGUUAUUCAUUCUUUUAAAAGAAUAAAUUAGUUUUAGACAUACAGAAUGCGUAACUAAUGUACAUAAUUAAUGUAUGCAACUUGAUGAGUGUGGAGAUACAUUAUCACCAGAAUCUAUGACAUCAACCUAUCUAUCACCUCCAAAAGUCUCAUCCAUUCUGCCCUCAUUUAUUACUUUUGUAAUAAGAACACUUAACAUAAGAUCUAUCAUUUUAGCAAUAAUUUAAGUAUACAAUAUUGUUAACUAUAGGCACCAUGCUGUACAGAUCUUGAGAACUUAUUCACCUUGUAUAAGGAAACUCUGUACCCCUUGACUAAUACCUCUGUUUUCCUCUCUUCCCAGCCCCUGACAACCACUUCUACAUCUAUGAGUUUGACAAUUUUAGAUUUAUUAUUCAUUAGGAUCUGUCUCAUAUGACACUGCUUUAAUUUCUUAAGUCUGAAUUAAGAAUUCUUCUCUCUGUACUCUAAAAUCACUUGUUUAUGUCUCAAUUUAGUAUUAUCAUUUUCCAUAUUUUGAACAAAAUAGUGUGGGUCAAAAACCAGCCUCUGCAGUCUGAUGGCCUGGGUUCAGAUCCUUGCUCUGAAGUUCGUUAUUUCUGCAACUAUAAGGAAGCUGAGCUUCAGUUUCUUUUUUGGAAAAUAAGGAUGAUAAUAUUACCUACUGCAUAAUAAUAUUAAGUGUUAAAUGAGAUAAUUCAAAUGAUGGAACACAAUUCUAGGCACACAGUGUUUCCUCAGGAAACAUUAGCUAAUUAUUUUUGCCUGUGUGUACUUUCCAUGAUUUUAAGUGUCCAUAUUGUUUGUUACUCAUCUUGUUGUCUUAAGACAUGUUUAUCAUUGUUAACUCAUACCCUAUCAUUUUGCUUUACACAAGCACUUAUGUGUAUGAGCUCCCCAAAUAUAUUUUAAACAGCCUAAGAUAAGGACUUAUAACUAUUAUUCUUUAGGAAUUUAUCUCCAAGAAUCUGAAUUGGCACCACGGUUAGACUAUCUCUCCAGUGAGGAGUUGUAAAAAAGUAGAUAUGCCUUUGAAACUUCAGGUCUAGCCCUCUGGUCAUCCUCUGUAGCACUAAAUGACUUGUUCCCUUCAGUCUUCAUGGAAUUCAUGAUGAGUUCAAAGACAAUAUAACUAACUUCUACUAGUGGAAAAAAUGGAGAACCAAGGAUUGAAUUUAUUCUGCCACCUUAAAUGUCUAAAAAAACAAAAAAACAAGAUCUAUGAAAUAACCACUUUCAAACACUGGACAUCAGGCUGUGUGGGAUCUCAUCUCUGAUAUCUGAGAAGAAAAUCAUAUGCGGUAACCCCUAUGGCUAUCUAGCUUACUGUAUGGCAUUUCCAAGGCAUAUCUCAGGGAGGGGAAACAGGCAGAACCUGGCAGUUUCCCUGAGUUGAGAAGACAAGCUGGGAGUUGUGGGAGGCCAAGAUGACUGGAGCCUGUAUGGCAGAGUACUAGGAUGAAGAGCGCCACAGGAGCACAGAGGAUCAGAGAUGUGCAGUGGGCAACCCUUGAGAUUUCAGCUUGGUCAAUGCAUGAGUAUAAUGAAACUGUUGAAAAGGAACAGGAAAAGAACUAUCGGAAAGGAGCAGAUGUAACAAUUUCUGAGGCUCAUACAGGACAGAAAAUGGUUUCAGUUCCCCAAAAUCCGACUAGAAAACUUCAUAAUUCAUGAAGUAUCAGGGAGACUACUCAGAAAGUAUUGCUUCCAUAGUGGGACAACAUUAGCCCUUGUUCUGGUCCCACCUAACAAAUAAAUGCAAGCUUUGAAAGUAUGAAAUGGUUUCCAUGUAAAAUAACAACGUACUGGAACAAAGCUCAAGAAUAUUGAUAGGAAUGUAAAAAUUUUUGGCACCCAAAGUUGUGAAAUUAACAAAGCUUGAUAUCUAGUCAAAAAUCAGGAAGUAUUUAAAACGUGGAAAAAAUAUGACCCACAAUGACUAGAAACAUCAGUGAAUAGAGACAGAUCCAGAAGUGAGAGAGAUGAUAGAACUAGUAGUCAGGAACAUUAAAAGUCAUUACCUUGAAUUUCUGGCCAAAAUGGAGUAACAGGGACUGGAUUUUCCCCUAGCCUGAAAACAAAACAAAACAAAACAAACAAAAAAGAGCGAAAUACAUGAAAUAAUGGUUUGCAAGGAACUAGACAUCAUGCAAUUAAAGAUGGUGACAACUGAGAUGCGUCCUAAAUUCCACUCCAGCAGACUACCGUGAGGGAUUCCAGGCCAGUGUCGCAAGGAAGGGCAGCAAGACAAAGACAAUUGGAAGUCCAGAUUUCAGAAGACAAAGCUGAGAGACCAAGGUGACAAGAGAUCACAGGCCACAAACCUGGCGGGUGACCUGCAGAGGCAGAGAGAGAGAGACAGAAAACUCAGGAUAUAUGAAGAGGUUUCCCCUAAAGUAUUCAACUGUGUACUGAUCAGAGCCCCGGCUGAGAAAACUUUCCAAGGCCAGGAAAGAACCACCCUAAAACUAUUAUGGUGUAACUUUCCUCCAACCCUCUCCCUGUACCUCUGUUAGGGAUCCCCAUUUCCUCAUUUCUAAAUUAAGGAGUUUGGCUCAGAUCAACCUUUUAUUGUUCCUGUGAAUUGGCUCCUCUGAGCUUUUUAAAAAAGGAUUCCACAUCCCACCUUCACAGACUCUGAUUCAGUAUGUCGGGGUGUAGCUAUGGAAUCUGCACUUUUACCUGCCUCAUCCCACAACCCCCGCCUCAAAUGAGCACCGCGUUGUUUAAACAACCGUCUAUGUGGCCACAGAAUGACCUCAAUGCUUUCCUAAAACUCCAGAACCUAUGAAGGUAACCUGUGCUUGCAGCUGUGCUUGCUUACAGAAACAAAGGCUGGAUGUCAGUAACCACCGUGCUACAAGAUGGGAAAGAGCUCAGCAGCGCUACCCUAACAUGAAUCUUUGCUAAUUACCAUACCUAAAUCUCUGCCCCGGGGAGAAAUGCACCUUGCUAGGCACAUGUAGUGCUGUGGUGCAACAGAAAGAAUGAGACUGCCACAUUCAGGUCUUCCUGGAAAGCCCCACCUCUUUCCAGGAAUCCUUGUCCUCAGUCUCCACCUAGGAGUCCUAAAAGACCUUAAAAAGCACCCCCUCACUACACCCCAGGAACUUUGAACAGGAGCUCUCCUGUUCCAUUCCCUGAUCAGUGAAUAAAGUUUCUGCUCUGCUUAACCGAACCUGGUCUCAUUCUAUGGGUGCAAAGGGCACCAGGGAAGGAAAGGAUCCACCAGGGUCAAACGACACUCUUGAGAUUCAGGAACACCCAGACGAUCUCCAUGUAUCUUUUCAGGAGUAACACUCUUGGCCUUUGAAGCUGAGAGGCAGGAAGGGAAUUACCACAACGGGCGGGGCCCAGCUCCCCAUCCAAAACCUCCUUGGUUUUGGGCUGAGAUCCUUCUGUCUACUGCCCCUGCCGGCCAUCCACCUAACUCCGGGUCCGACCCAGAACCAGAAAAACCACUCAAAGAACCGGCGAGCCUGACCAGACAGUGCACGUGCUAGUGCCCGCUGCUCCCGAUUCGCAGGUGUUGGGAAGACUUCUCUCUUGCCUGUCUAAGCUGAACUUUUCCCGCCUGGAAGAGCAGGCUGGCGCGCGGGAGGGAGCCUGGGAAUUGACACUCUCGCUGGCCAAUGGACGAAGAGUCUCUGGAGGCUGUUUUCUCUCAUUGGAUGGAAAUGAUUCAUCCUCUCAUCCACUUUGGAAGCUAAUUCGCAUCACUCCAGACAGUGAUUGAAGAGAGGAAAAGGGAUGAGAGUGCACGCCUGGGCGCACGCGCUCGCGGGCGGGUCAGACGGCCAGGCCGAGGGGACUGCGCGCCCACCCGCCCACCCUCCCUAUUUGUCCAGAUGACCCAUCCCGGUCCCAGCGAUCCCCUCCCCCGAACCACUCGGUCCACAGCCAGUUCCCGCGUACCAGGAUAAACUAAGCAGUCACUGCCCUGCUUCUUCCUGCUCAUCGGCGUCCCCUGUCUCCCAGUGGAAGCCAAGGAGGGGUUGCGCGGCAGCCGGGUGGGUAUGGGAGAUGCCUGGCGGUUUCGCGCUUUUUCCGCCUUUUGAUUGCGAGUGGGAGCAGCGCGCUGAGGAGAGCUGCAAGGGGAAUAGCCCGCCAAGGUGCUUCGGUGUGUGGCCAUUGCUGCCCUUCUGCCGCUGAUGGGUCGGCGGCGGUGGCGGGACGUGCAUCCAGGCGGGAUCCAGCGGCAGCAGCAGAGAGAGCUCCACCCUGAUGAUGCAGAGGCCCAGCUUCCAGCUGACUGCAAGUCGCAGAGCAGGCUGCACCCGCGUCUGCGUGAGGUCUAGAGGGACUUGGCCUGCUCCGCAAAUGAUCCAACUUCGUGGAGGGGCUGGCGAACACAGACAAUGCCAGUCUGGACGAGGAAGGGGCCAGCACUGCUUAGGCCUGUUUCCCAGGACGCGCAUUACUGGGUGCGGAACUUUACCCCUCAGAUGAAGAGUAUUUAGGCCUGUUUCCCAGGAGGCGCAUUACUGGGUGUGGAACUUUACCCUUCGGAUGAAGACUCCAGAGUUGGGUAUCUCCAAAGUGAUAAUCAAAUCAUCUUCUUGAGGGAAAGAAGCUGAAGUGCUACAUAAGAUGCUUGUGCUUCAUAACUCUCAGAAGCUGCAGAUUCUGUAUAAAUCCUUAGAAAAGAGCAUCCCUGAAUCCAUAAAGGUAUAUGGCGCCAUUUUCAACAUAAAAGAUAAAAACCCUUUCAACAUGGAGGUGCUGGUAGAUGCCUGGCCAGAUUACCAGAUCGUCAUUACCCGGCCUCAGAAACAGGAGAUGAAAGAUGACCAGGAUCAUUAUACCAACACUUACCACAUCUUCACCAAAGCUCCUGACAAAUUAGAGGAAGUCCUGUCAUACUCCAAUGUAAUCAGCUGGGAGCAAACUUUGCAGAUCCAAGGUUGCCAAGAGGGCUUGGAUGAAGCAAUAAGAAAGGUUGCAACUUCAAAAUCAGUGCAGGUAGAUUACAUGAAAACCAUCCUCUUUAUACCGGAAUUACCAAAGAAACACAAGACCUCAAGUAAUGACAAGAUGGAGUUAUUUGAAGUGGAUGAUGAUAACAAGGAAGGAAACUUUUCAAACAUGUUCUUAGAUGCUUCACAUGCAGGUCUUGUGAAUGAACACUGGGCCUUUGGGAAAAAUGAGAGGAGCUUGAAAUAUAUUGAACGCUGCCUCCAGGAUUUUCUAGGAUUUGGUGUGCUGGGUCCAGAGGGCCAGCUUGUCUCUUGGAUUGUGAUGGAACAGUCCUGUGAGUUGAGAAUGGGUUAUACUGUCCCCAAAUACAGACACCAAGGCAACAUGUUGCAAAUUGGUUAUCAUCUUGAAAAGUAUCUUUCUCAGAAAGAAAUCCCAUUUUAUUUCCAUGUGGCAGAUAAUAAUGAGAAAAGCCUACAGGCACUGAACAAUUUGGGGUUUAAGAUUUGUCCUUGUGGCUGGCAUCAGUGGAAAUGCACCCCCAAGAAAUAUUGUUGAUUGAUUCCACUGUCCAUUUCAAAUCUUUCUUAUCAGUAAAAAAACAUUAAUUCAAACACAAGCAUUGUGAUCUACAUUAGCACAAAAUGCAACUGAUUAUCUAGGAUCUGUGUAUUACUUAAGCUCACCCUUAACAGUUUUACCUUCCUUCUCCUCUGUAUUCUUACAGAAAAUUAGAAGCUCAAUUUUAUGGUCUCAUAAUUUCCUUUAUGACAGACAUCUCAGAAUUAAAAUCACCCAAAGCCAAUCAUUAGUGCCAAGAUAACCCUUUAACGGCAACACUUUCUUAAAUGAAGACUAUUUCUUUCAUGAAAAAAUUCACUUUUAUGACUUUCUUGUUAAAAUAAAAAGUCUGCUUUUAAAA